GGACUCGGCGACUAGGCGCCGCCUGACCAGUAGGAGCCGCCCUCGACGAGCGAGCUCGAAGGCUGCGACUGGCGCCGCCUCACCGCCUCCCACCGCCACUGACCGACCGUUCGACCGGCAAACAUGGUUGAAGCGGAUCGCCCGGGGAAGCUGUUCAUUGGGGGCCUCAACCUCGAAACCGACGAGAAAGCCCUCGAAGCCGAGUUUGGCAAGUAUGGCCGCAUCGUCGAGGUGCUCCUGAUGAAAGACCGAGAAACCAACAAGUCGAGGGGCUUCGCGUUCGUCACCUUUGAAAGCCCCGCAGACGCCAAGGCCGCCGCCAGAGACAUGAACGGCAAGUCCCUGGAUGGUAAGGCCAUCAAGGUGGCCCAGGCCACCAAACCGGCGUUCGAGAGCAGCCGGCGGGGCCCGCCGCCUCCCCGCAGCCGCGGUCGCCCGAGGUUCCUGCGCGGAACCCGCGGGGGUGGCGGCGGCCCGCGGCGUUCCCCAUCCCGGGGCGGGCCCGAUGAUGACGGCGGCUACACGGCGGAUUUCGACCUGCGGCCCUCCAGGGCCCCGAUGCCCAUGAAGCGUGGGCCGCCGCCGCGCAGGGUCGGCCCACCCCCCAAGAGGGCCGCGCCGUCGGGCCCGGCUCGCAGCAGCGGCGGUGGAAUGCGCGGGAGGGCCCUGGCCGUGCGGGGGCGAGACGGCUACUCAGGCCCACCGCGCCGGGAGCCGCUGCCCCCGCGCCGCGACCCCUACCUGGGCCCGCGGGAUGAGGGCUACUCGUCCAGAGACGGCUACUCGAGCCGAGACUACCGCGAACCCCGGGGUUUUGCCCCCUCGCCCGGAGAGUACACCCACCGCGAUUACGGCCACUCCAGUGUCCGGGACGACUGUCCCUUGAGAGGCUACAGCGACCGAGACGGCUACGGAGGUCGCGACCGUGACUACGGGGAUCAUCUGAGCAGAGGCUCCCAUCGAGAGCCCUUUGAGAGCUACGGAGAGCUGCGCGGCGCCGCCCCAGGACGGGGGACACCGCCAUCUUACGGAGGAGGAGGCCGCUACGAGGAGUACCGGGGCUACUCACCCGAUGCCUACAGCGGCGGCCGCGACAGUUACAGCAGCAGUUAUGGCCGGAGCGACCGCUACUCGAGGGGCCGACACCGGGUGGGCAGACCAGAUCGUGGGCUCUCUCUGUCCAUGGAAAGGGGCUGCCCUCCCCAGCGUGAUUCUUACAGCCGGUCAGGCUGCAGGGUGCCCAGGGGCGGAGGCCGUCUAGGAGGCCGCUUGGAGAGAGGAGGAGGCCGGAGCAGAUACUAAGCAGGAACAGACUUGGGACCAAAAAUCCCUUUUCAACGAAACUAACAAAAAGAAGAACCUGUUGUAUGGUAACUACCCAAGGACUAGUACAAGGAAGAGUUGUUUUUACCUUUUAAGAAUUUCCUGUUAAGAUCGUCUCCAUUUUUAUGCUUUUGGGAGAAAAAACUUAAAAUUCGUUUAGUUUAGUUUUGGAAUUGUUAACGUUUCUUUCAACAAGCUCCUGUUAAAAGUAUAUGAACCUGAGUACUAGUCUUCUUACAUUUACAAGUAGAAAUUCGAUUAAUGGCUUCUUCCCUUGUAAAUUUUCUUGAUAAAUGAGGCAAACAGUUCUAAGAUCUUUGAUAAACAUCUGCUCACCUAAAAUGGAAAAACGGAUCAUUCUGCUCAUUUAAACCAACUAGAUUUUGGGUGGAGAGUGGGAGGGAUUGGUGUAUGCUACUCUUAAGAUUUCAGGGUAUCUUUCAAACUGAAUCUUUGUUUCCAGUAUUAAAAAGCAAACAACCAGCAACAACAACAACAAAAGUGAUUUAGAUCAAAUGUUUAUGUAAAGAAAAUUAUUUUCACUCAGUAAAUCUGAAAAGUAAAUGGAUAAUGUUGGCCAUGUUUUGCCUUUUUGCUUUUUCUUUGGGAAUCUACAGGAUCACCUGUCCCCUCACUCCCAAAAGUACUAUCUAUGUUUUGAACAACAGUGGAAUACUAUAUCAAAGGUUUGGCCAACCAACCACAAAGCUACAAAACAAGCAAAUCCCAAAUCCUUCAAUUGAUAGCAUUCAUUUUCACUACCAACAAAUUUAUUAAGAAACAAGUAGAAAAUAAAUCAGUGGUCGACUUGGGGACCGUAAUGGCUUC